CUCCCUCCCCAGCCCCUCCACCGCCUCCCUCCGCCGCCGCUUGGGCCGGCUCCGCGCCCCCUCCGCGGCCCCCGCCCGCCCGCCUGCCCGCCGCCCCCAUGGCGCCCGGGGUCCCCGCUGCACGGGGCCACUAGGACCCUCGGCGUCCCUUCCCCUCCCCCGCCCUGCCCCCUCUCCCGCCGCGCGGACCCGGGCGUUCUCGGCGCCCAGCUUUUGAGCUCGCGUCCCCAGGCCGGCGGGGGGGGAGGGGAAGAGAGGGGACCCUGGGACCCCCGCCCCCCCCACCCGGCCGCCCCUGCCCCCCGGGACCCGGAGAAGAUGUCUUCGCGGACGGUGCUGGCCCCGGGCAACGAUCGGAACUCGGACACGCAUGGCACCUUGGGCAGUGGCCGCUCCUCGGACAAAGGCCCGUCCUGGUCCAGCCGCUCACUGGGUGCCCGUUGCCGGAACUCCAUCGCCUCCUGUCCCGAGGAGCAGCCCCACGUGGGCAACUACCGCCUGCUGAGGACCAUUGGGAAGGGCAACUUUGCCAAAGUCAAGCUGGCUCGGCACAUCCUCACUGGUCGGGAGGUUGCCAUCAAGAUUAUCGACAAAACCCAGCUGAAUCCCAGCAGCCUGCAGAAGCUGUUCCGAGAAGUCCGCAUCAUGAAGGGCCUAAACCACCCCAACAUCGUGAAGCUCUUUGAGGUGAUUGAGACUGAGAAGACGCUGUACCUGGUGAUGGAGUACGCAAGUGCUGGAGAAGUGUUUGACUACCUCGUGUCGCAUGGCCGCAUGAAGGAGAAGGAAGCUCGAGCCAAGUUCCGACAGAUUGUUUCGGCUGUGCACUAUUGUCACCAGAAAAAUAUUGUACACAGGGACCUGAAGGCUGAGAACCUCUUGCUGGAUGCCGAGGCCAACAUCAAGAUUGCUGACUUUGGCUUCAGCAACGAGUUCACGCUGGGAUCGAAGCUGGACACGUUCUGCGGGAGCCCCCCAUAUGCCGCCCCGGAGCUGUUUCAGGGCAAGAAGUACGACGGGCCGGAGGUGGACAUCUGGAGCCUGGGAGUCAUCCUGUACACCCUCGUCAGCGGCUCCCUGCCCUUCGACGGGCACAACCUCAAGGAGCUGCGGGAGCGAGUACUCAGAGGGAAGUACCGGGUCCCUUUCUACAUGUCAACAGACUGUGAGAGCAUCCUGCGGAGAUUUUUGGUGCUGAACCCAGCUAAACGCUGUACUCUCGAGCAAAUCAUGAAAGACAAAUGGAUCAACAUCGGCUAUGAGGGUGAGGAGUUGAAGCCAUACACAGAGCCCGAGGAGGACUUCGGGGACACCAAGAGAAUUGAGGUGAUGGUGGGUAUGGGCUACACACGGGAAGAAAUCAAAGAGUCCUUGACCAGCCAGAAGUACAACGAAGUGACCGCCACCUACCUCCUGCUGGGCAGGAAGACUGAGGAGGGUGGGGACCGGGGCGCCCCAGGGCUGGCCCUGGCACGGGUGCGGGCGCCCAGCGACACCACCAACGGAACAAGUUCCAGCAAAGGCACCAGCCACAGCAAAGGGCAGCGGAGUUCCUCUUCCACCUACCACCGCCAGCGCAGGCAUAGCGAUUUCUGUGGCCCAUCCCCUGCACCCCUGCACCCCAAACGCAGCCCGACGAGCACGGGGGAGGCGGAGCUGAAGGAGGAGCGGCUGCCAGGCCGGAAGGCGAGCUGCAGCACCGCGGGGAGUGGGAGUCGAGGGCUGCCCCCCUCCAGCCCCAUGGUCAGCAGCGCCCACAACCCCAACAAGGCAGAGAUCCCAGAGCGGCGGAAGGACAGCACGAGCACCCCCAACAACCUCCCUCCUAGCAUGAUGACCCGCAGAAACACCUACGUUUGCACAGAACGCCCGGGGGCUGAGCGCCCGUCACUGUUGCCAAAUGGGAAAGAAAACAGCUCAGGCACCCCACGGGUGCCCCCUGCCUCCCCCUCCAGUCACAGCCUGGCACCCCCAUCAGGGGAGCGGAGCCGCCUGGCACGUGGUUCCACCAUCCGCAGCACCUUCCAUGGUGGCCAGGUCCGGGACCGGCGGGCAGGGGGUGGGGGUGGUGGGGGUGUGCAGAAUGGGCCCCCUGCCUCUCCCACACUGGCCCAUGAGGCUGCACCCCUGCCCGCCGGGCGGCCCCGCCCCACCACCAACCUCUUCACCAAGCUGACCUCCAAACUGACCCGAAGGGUUACCCUCGAUCCCUCUAAACGGCAGAACUCUAACCGCUGUGUUUCGGGCGCCUCUCUGCCCCAGGGAUCCAAGAUCAGGUCGCAGACGAACCUGAGAGAAUCGGGGGACCUGAGGUCACAAGUUGCCAUCUACCUUGGGAUCAAACGGAAACCGCCCCCCGGCUGCUCCGAUUCCCCUGGAGUGUGAAGCUGACCAGCUCGCGCCCUCCUGAGGCCCUGAUGGCAGCUCUGCGCCAGGCCACAGCAGCCGCCCGCUGCCGCUGCCGCCAGCCACAGCCGUUCCUGCUGGCCUGCCUGCACGGGGGUGCGGGCGGGCCCGAGCCCCUGUCCCACUUCGAAGUGGAGGUCUGCCAGCUGCCCCGGCCAGGCUUGCGGGGAGUUCUCUUCCGCCGUGUGGCGGGCACCGCCCUGGCCUUCCGCACCCUCGUCACCCGCAUCUCCAACGACCUCGAGCUCUGAGCCACCACGGUCCCAGGGCCCUUACUCUUCCUCUCCCUUGUCGCCUUCACUUCUACAGGAGGGGAAGGGGCCAGGGAGGGGAUUCUCCCUUUAUCAUCACCUCAGUUUCCCUGAAUUAUAUUUGGGGGCAAAGAUUGUCCCCUCUGCUGUUCUCUGGGGCCGCUCAGCACAGAAGAAGGAUGAGGGGGCUCAGCGGGGGGAGCUGGCACCUUCCUGGAGCCUCCAGCCAGUCCUGUCCUCCCUCGCCCUACCAAGAGGGCACCUGAGGAGACUUUGGGGACAGGGCAGGGGCAGGGAGGGAAACUGAGGAAAUCUUCCAUUCCUCCCAACAGCUCAAAAUUAGGCCUUGGGCAGGGGCAGGGAGAGCUGCUGAGCCUAAAGACUGGAGAAUCUGGGGGACUGGGAGUGGGGGUCAGAGAGGCAGAUUCCUUCCCCUCCCGUCCCCUCACGCUCAAACCCCCACUUCCUGCCCCAGGCUGGCGCGGGGCACUUUGUACAAAUCCUUGUAAAUACCCCACACCCUCCCCUCUGCAAAGGUCUCUUGAGGAGCUGCCGCUGUCACCUACGGUUUUUAAGUUAUUACACCCCGACCCUCCUCCUGUCAGCCCCCUCACCUGCAGCCUGUUGCCCAAUAAAUUUAAGAGAGUCCCCCCCUCCCCAAUGCUGACCCUAGGAUUUUCCUUCCCUGCCCUCACCUGCAAAUGAGUUAAAGAAGAGGCGUGGGAAUCCAGGCAGUGGUUUUUCCUUUCGGAGCCUCGGUUUUCUCAUCUGCAGAAUGGGAGCGGUGGGGGUGGGAAGGUAAGGAUGGUCGUGGAAGAAGGCAGGAUGGAACUCGGCCUCAUCCCCGAGGCCCCAGUUCCUAUAUCGGGCCCCCCAUUCAUCCACUCACACUCCCAGCCACCAUGUUACACUGGACUCUAAGCCACUUCUUACUCCAGUAGUAAAUUUAUUCAAUAAACAAUCAUUGACCCAUGCCUACUCCAUGCCAGGCCCAGUGCUGGACACAGAGACAUGAAGCUCUGUCUGUGGGAGACAGGGAUUCUGACACAGACACCGGACAAACCAUUGUCUUGGGGAGCCCAGAAGAGAAAGUGGGCAGGGUGGGGUCAUUGGGGAAGAUGCUCUAGAGGAAUUAAUGCUGGAAUGGGGUGUUGAAGGAUGAGUAGGAGUUAGUUAGGCAUUGAGUUUGCCCUGGGCAAAAGCCCAGAAGUGGGAGUAUGUGGUAUAUCUUCAGAGAACUGGGUAAUUUCAGUGUGGCUGCUGUGUUGGGCAUGGAUGGAGAAUCAGCAAGAGAAAUGCUGUAUUAGGACUAAUAAUCCAUCUACGCUGCUUAAGCAAAAAGGUAUUUGUUGGUUUAUGUUACUUAAUAGUCCAGGGGCACCUGGCUUCAGGUAGGUUUGAUCCAGGCAUCAGGCCAUUGCAUCUAUUUUUUCAGUGUAAGUUGAAUUCUAGUAAUUUUUAUCAAGUAAGGGCUCCUUUCCUGGUGGCACAGAUGACUUCAGCAGUUAGAAGUUUCUAUCCCUCCAGCUUUCUGCAGCAGAAAGACCCUCAUUGUCAGUUUCCCAGCAAAAGUCCCAGGGCAGACUCUCAUUGGCCCAAAUGGGCCAUGUGAUUUUCUCUAAACCAAUCACUGUGACUCUAGAGUGGCCAGACUCAGAGCUGCACUUAGUAGGGGUUCCUCAAAGGAAGGUCAAGUGUCAUGAGCAGGAGAAAAGGCAUGGGAGCUGGACAGAUUAUAGUGGUUGAAGUCUGUGCAGUACAGAAGGGCGGAGCUUAUUCACACAGCACCUUUGGGGCCAAAAUGAAUAAGCUGGACUUUCUCCCCAUGGCACUGGGGAACCAUGGAAGUUCAGGGAACUUCAGGGAAGAGGCUUGGUCAAUUCCUGAGAGCAUCCUCUGUGCUGGGGACACAGUGGUAAUCAAGACAGCCCCAACACUGCCCUCAUAGAGCUCACAGUCCAAUGGAGGAGGCAGAUGUGUCCUCAGGCAGCGACUGGGCAGGGCUGGUAUAGGGGAGUCCAGAGGUGAUGCCUGCCUCAGCCAGGGAGGGCUUCCUGGAGGAGAAGGAGCCAGCUAGACAUGGAUAGGAGUGCGUUUUAGGCACAGCAAAUGGCACAUACAAGGGCCAGGGAGCAAGAGAGAGGACAGGUCCUCAACAAAUGGCAUGUGACUUUGUAAGUGUAGAAUUGCUGUGAGGUAUGGGGCUAGGGGCGUCAGUAGGGCCUUGAAGGUUAUGGACAGGGGCCUGGGCUUUCUUCCAAGGGCACUGGGGGAGCCAUGGCAAGGUUGUAGGUAGGGUAGAGAUGGGCGGGUUUGUGCUAUGUGCAGGGUGGAAGGGAGGGAAGUUGACAGGUCAGAAGAUCAGGAAAGAGGUCGGGGCUGGACAGAUGGGGAGAGCGCAGAUAGAUUUAAGAGAGUCCUGUGAGGCAAAGUGGGCAGGACCUGGUAACAGGUGUCUGGACUGUGGCUUUGGCUGGCUCAGAAGGUCCCCACUGGCGUGUGUGGUCUAUGUAGCCUCUGGGUGUGGAGCUGGGAUCUUCAACUGGGGACAGUACAGUAAAGAACAUCACAGCA